AGUGAGGAGUCAGCCGGGCAGCCAGCCAGCGAGCCAGCCAGCCAGCCAGCCAGCCAGCCAGCCAACCAGCCAGCCAGCGGGCCACCCAGCGGCCGCUGCAGCCGCCGCCGCCGCACAAGGGCAGACGCGCUGCGGUGCGGGGCUCGGGCCGGGGCGCUCGGUGCCCUAGCUCCUCGCCGCGCCAGCCGCCUCGCAGCCAACAAGAUGUUCUGUUUUUCUCUAGUAAAAACAGCAGAGAAUCCAAAACCUGUUAAGUCAGCCAUCACUUCUGAGGAUCACAUGAAGUUAAGUUUGAAGAACAUUUUCUAUGUUUUUUUCUAGAGGAAAAAUAACUGAAACUACAAUAGGAAAAAAAUUAUCAGGAGUCAGGAAGAAAACAAGAAAAAUGCAGUUCAGUGAAAUGUUGUCACUAAAGCCAGAGCACUAAACUCAUGAAUAUGACAGAGCGGGUUGGGAGAAUGUGGUGCAAGGGAGAUUGUACCUAAAAGGAAUCCAGUAAUCUGAAGGGUGGCCCCAUCCUCUACCAACUUGACACCUUUGUGAAUUCAAGUUAUGAGAUUUGCUCAUUAUCUGUGGAUACAUUCUCUACAGCAAAAUGUACUUGGAGUGGUGCUGUCCCUGCCACCGGGCCCACAUCUAUACAACUUCCCAUAUGGGGACUGCAAAGCUGUUAAAGCUCAGGUUGGAGCUAAGAAACUGUAUUUGUAGUAAUGGGUCACAUUGGAUGAACUGAGUCCUUGAUCCCAUGGUGCAGUUAAUAUGAACUAGGCCUCCCUAUGUUGCAGUUUUGUGUAACUCUCAGAAUGCCCUUCUUUAUCUGGGUAUUUGCAUGUUAUUCUUUGCAGGCAAGAUAACUUUGCUAACACUUUGAAGAUUUGUUAGGAAAGAGUUGAUGACUUUGUCCAGAUUGUAAUUCUUUUUCCUUUGAGAGGAGAAGGAUUAAAUAACAAAGCAUUUUGUGUACUGGGUAGGUUAUGGUUUGAUUAAUGUGAUUUUACUCACUGCCCAAGUAAGCAGCUGAUAGGAGCCAUAAACCUGGGGUCAAGCUUAUAAAUUAGAUACGUCCAAGAGAGGCAGGGUGUUACAGUCUUGAGGAACAACUUCCCUCCCUCUUAGUGCACCUGUCACAUAAUGUGAGUGGCUAGGAAGUGAAGAGCAGGUGAACUAAUGAUGCUGGGAGACCCAAAUCACAAGUGUGAAUUAGCCAAGCACCAAAGGUUAUGUUGGAUUGAGUAGCAAGGGGAGAUUGAAACCAAGGUUAAUAUGCCAGUGAUUUAGGCUCGUGUCUGCCCUUAACUGGUGUGUUCAUGGGCAAUUUACUUAACCUUUCUUGGUCUCCAUUGCCUGACUCAUCUGUAAAAUAGGGUGUUAGGUGAGAUCACCAAAGUGGUGAUCUCAGGCAGGUUCCAUUUGCUAGGUCCCUCGCUCUCCAUAUGUGUUUGAAAUUUACUGAUAUUUUUGUCUGUGCUACUCCCUGCUUUUGGACUUACUGCCAUUAUCUUCUCUUUUCCACCAGCACGCCAAAAGAUCUUGUGGCAUAUAGUGGUGAAACUGCUCUUAUCCCCCUUACCCAAAACCACUCUGUAUCAUUUUUGAAUUGUUAUGAUAAGGAAAUGUAUCAUGAGUCCUUUGUAAUAGUGGUUUAUAACAGGGUUUUUGUUUUCGUUCCACGGAUCCUUUCAGAGUCCAAGAAAAAGCUAUGGGCCUUCUCAUCAGGAGAAAGUGUCUACAGACACAUUUCCGUAUGGUUGCAGGGAGUUCACGGAUUCUGAAGGCCCUCAGGCUAAGAACUCAUGCUCAAGAAAAAUACCAUUACUCUAUUUGCAAGUUUGUGUAGUACUGUUGCUCUCUUUGGGAAAUGCUAGGAACUAAAGGUAAGGAACCCAGACUGAACCUGAUGAAUGACUUAGUAACGUGAUGUUCAAGUUAUGAAUGAGUCCCAGACACGCAAGCCUCCUUCUUGAGAUAGAUGCAUCACUUCCUGGAGGAAAGCUGUGUCCUGUGACUGGGUGUGUGCAUCCUAGAUUUACUGUGCACCAUUGGCUGAAACAGAAAAUAUCUGUGAGCUUUCAGUUCUCAUGUAAAGUAGGAGCAUAAUAUCUUCUAGUUGCUCUCUUCGUAGUGUGAUAUGAAGCAAUUUGACUGGCAUCCUCAGAGUUUCUCUGAGCACUGUCUGACAACACUAUCUAAAUUUAAAAGUUCUCAGUUUGGGCUAGUAAAGUACUGUUCCUGUCAGAGUUCAUCUCAUGGAGAUCACAUUUUCAUAAAUCACUACUGUGUUAUCUUCCUUUUCAUCUGUACAUGAUCUUCCAUUUUUCAUCCCCUUAGAAGGUGAUUCUAGGGAGGACCAAUAAUUGAUGUACUUAAUCUACUGGACACUCACAUCCUUUCAUUAGUUUGUCUGUCCUGGGGAUAAAGCAUUCCCCUAAUAGAAUUGUCACAACUAGGACCCCUAAUCCAGUUUAUUCCUUCUUGGUUUGGAGUGUAGAGUUGCUGCAUUAAUGGUGGAAAUAAACAAGUUCUGGUGGGCAGGAUCAUUUUUUAGUUGUUUGGAAAUAUAAAAGUAGAUGAAAAUGGAAACAGAAUCUGAUUCUAUUUUGAACAUAACAGCUAUUCCUUUAUCUCAUUUUUAAAAAGAGCAAAAAGCAUCAAACUUAAGUUUCUAUUAGUAUCUUUGCUCCACUGCCCCUUCUCCCACUUCCCAUGAGCUCUGUUCAGUAUUAAGCCUUGUAACCACUCUUGUUCUGGCAUGAUUUAUAAAAGCAGGCUAUUCCUUUUAUGGAAAUCACUGAUAUUUUAUUAUGUUCUGGCCAAAACUUAAAUGAACAUAAAUAACCCAAAAUUUCAGAAAAAAAUAUAAUUAUCCAUUUCAAAACUUUUUAUAAGCUUUCUAGUAAAUAUAUAAAAGUAGAUAAAGUAGUGUAAUAAGCCUAUAUAUACCACCAUCCAGCUUCAACAGUGGUCAAUAUAUGACCAAUAUUGUUUCAUCUGUACCCCAGCCCCUUCCCCUUUGUCCGGGAGUUAUGUUGAAGCAAAUUCUAGACAUAUCAUUUCACUUGUAAAUAUUUCAUUAUAUAUCUCUUAAAGAUAUAAGAACUCUUUGUACACUUAAUCUCAGUACCAACACCUGACAAAAUGAAGUUCCUUGAUAUCAAAUAUCUAAUUAGUAUUCACAGUUCCUCCGUUGUCUUAUAAUUUGUUUCUGUAAUUUGUAAGUUUGAGUUGGCAUUCAAAUAAGGUCAGUAUAUUGGGGUUGGUUGAUAUUGUUUAUGUUUUUUGACCUACAGGUCUCUCUACUUUCCCCUUUCUUUGCCAUUUUUGUCACUGUUGCAUUGUUAUUGAAGAAAGUGGAUCAUGUGUGUUACAUUCUUUCCUAUGAUCUGGUUUUUGCUGAUAAUCUGUUAUUUUUAAGGAAAUAAGAGUAACAGGUAUGUAAUUAUUUCAAACCUGUUUUUAAGUGUAUGCAAAUGUUUUACUUCAUGCUGAAAACUAGCUGUGGAAGUUAACACUUAAUUAGGCAGGAAAAUUCAGGCAUCAGGUGACUUCUUUACAUUUUUAUUCCUGUUUUUUCUUUUUGGAAGAUAUCUUGGCAGAUUAUAGGGAGAGGUGUCACUUACCCACUGCUGAAAUGCACUGGGCUGGAACACGCCAGCCAUUCUUCAUCAACAACACCAAACAGUUAUUUUGGGCAAAGAAUUAGAAGAGCGGUUGUUUUGUUGUUGUUGAAUAUACAGUGGGAAGCUGGGGUGAUUGAAUGUGUGCCUCAAGUCCUUUGGCCCCAACACCCCUCUCUCCUUAUUUGCUAUGAUAAGCAUUCUCUUGAGGGCUAUUCAUUACAGUGGAAAUAUGAUCACAGAAUCAUCUGGGUUGGAAAAGACUUCCUGAGGUCACCUGGCCCCAUCUGGCAACGUUAAUAUGGGAUUCCAGCAUCAACUUUCCCAGAACAAGGCUGUCUGUUAACAACUCACAUAGCUCACAUAAACCCCUGGUGCAGUCUUAACCUGUUUUCUCUUUUGUCCUUCAGUGAAAUAGAUGAUUAAAUUGCAUGUCUUUCUGCUGUAGGAGUGUUACACAACUAGGACCCCAAUCCAGAUAACACACACAUGUGGCUGUGUAGAUCUUUAAGAUUAAUCUUGAUUUUUCCCUGCCAUCCUCUAUAGCACAUAUACCCUGAGACUCUAUUCAACUAUCUGUAUGUAGUAAUGAUUUUCAUGAAAAAUGUUUAAAUGCGUAAAUAUGAUGCAAUUACUGCAGACUACACCUUUAAGCUACAGUAUGUAUGAUGGUUAAUUUUAUGUGUCAAUUUGGCUGGGCCACAGAAUGCCAAGAUUUGUGGUCAAACAUUAUUCUGGGUGUUUUGUGAGUAUGUUUUUUAGAUGAGGAUAACAUAUAAAUCAGUGGACUUCGAGUACAUUGCCCACCAUAAUGUGGGUGGGCCUCAUCCAAUCAGCUGAAACCUGAAUAGAACAAACAGACUGAUCUUCAGAGGAAUCUUCUGCAUCUGCUCUCUUGGGUCUCCAGCCUGUCAGCUGACCCUACAGAUUUUGGACUUGCCAGACCCCAUAAUGGCAUGAGCCAGUUCUUUAUGAUAAAUCAAUCUCUCUCUCUCUCUCUCUCUAUACACACACACACACACACACACACACACACACACACAUCCUAUUGGUUCUCUUAGGAGGACCCUGAUUAAUCAGUGUGCAAAAACAAAAAGAAAAGACAAGUAUAUGUCCUCAAUUUAUCUGGCUAUUUUUUGAAGAUGUGUUUUAUAUUAAAGAGAUGCAAAGAUCACUGGAGACACCAUCCGCAAAAUUGAGAGUCUGGCCACAACUCUUCUAGUAAAACCUGACUUUCAGUCACUUUCCCUUUCUAGCCUUAGUUUCAUCUCUGUAAAAGAAGGUUAAACGAAGGGAUUUCCAAGGUCUGUGAUUUCCUGAAAUGCAAACAUGGAACAUUUGAGCCAGCUGCUGAGAAAGUGUCUAGAGAUAAUAAUUCUGAGGGCUGCCCAAAGUUUCUCUUACUAAACAAAACAACUGAGGGUGUAAAACAGUAGUGGUGGUGGAGCACAGGGAAUAAAAAACCAUCAACAGAAGGAUUUCCUGUAUAUAAGGAAAAUAUACAGGAAAAUGGAUCACCCUGAUUUAUGUCGCGGAAGAUUCUAAUCAGUUAAAUGUAAAAUAUGGAUAGUAAAUGCCAACGGGAAAACCUGUAGCUUUUGUGACUUCUCAGCUGAGGGCAGAUAGUCUAACUUUGAGGGCACUUAGGAUCUGUGUCUGCGUUGCACUAAUUCUUAUUUCGUGCAGGAGGAAUAGGGUGGUGGUGGAGGAUUGGCAUUUGUGAUAAGCUGAGGCUGUCAAGCCAAACUGAGGGGCCCUAGCCCAACCGAUGGACAGGAAAUGUCUGACCCCAAGGGCAUUUGUGCUAUUCCUGAUCACAGAGAUUGGAAGGAGCCUCAAACUGGUGCUGACCCAUGGGGAUGUAGGUUGGUUUCUCUGUUGCCUUGGUUUUGAGCCUUUUUGUUUUUCCACCUUGGGCUUCCCUCUCCAGGUAAAAAAAGCAGUAACCACAAGGCAGAAACCAUAUUAUUUUAGCUCCUCUUGUCUGGAGAGCGGGCAACACUUAGGUGCAGUAAUCUUUUGGCUGUCCCUGUCUGGAAUUAAUGUUCACCCUCACGCAGCAGUCUGCCACUUGGGUGGCUGGCAUUUUGGGUUGGGCAGUCUGGGUUUGUGCCUGGCCAAGCCAGCUGAGGGGAAGUUCGCCUGCCACGUUUGGUUGUGGACACAUUCUGUGUAAGGUGCUUACCCCUUGCUCAGUAGAGGCAUCCCCUGCAAAUAUGGCGAGGUGGCUUUCUUUGCCCUUUGGGUUCCUUUUGACCAUAAACUUAGCAGUGAGGAGGCAGGACCUUGAUGGUCAUAUCCCCCGAGAGGCUAGCUGACUUUUUACCCAGUUGGUGCUGAAGAUGGACAAAUGAUUAACCCCCUGGAAUCUCUGGUUAGACCCCAGUUGUGGUCAUGAGUUCAGCCUUUUGAACCGCAGGCUGAAAUUGUUUUUCCAGCGCUCUACCCAAUCGGGUGUCCCCGCCUGGACUCUGCUAUGGAAGCGCUCCCUUGGGAAAUAGUGGUGGGCAGGGGGGCGUGGGAAGAGGAGGGAGGAAGCCUCCAGCUGCUGCUGGCCGGCCCUGCGUUCCUCUGAGGAGGUAGGGAAGGGACCCUCGAGAUGAGUGGGAGACAGGAAAGGAGCUGCAGUCUGGAGGCCCGAGUGGGAGCCGCUCCUGGCCCGCCGCCCGCCGGGCCGCUUCCUUCCCCUGACAUGACAGCCCUGCCGGCCUGGCUCCCCGCCACCUGGCAGCGGCCGCCGCGGCACAUGACUCCUCCGCCCUCUGCCCUGGGGGCUGGCGGGGCCCAGGCGGGGCCCAAGCGGGGCCCAAGCGGGGGCUGGGAGUGAUCUGCUCUGGAACUGGCCGUCCCUGCUGGUCGGGGCUGCCAGGUGCGGCCCGCGCUGCUUCGCUGGGAACUGGCCUUCCUCUUCCAGUCCUAACGCGCUUGGCCAUUUGUCCCUUCUAGGAGCCAGCGGAGGGGAACACCUGCUGUCUCUACCUGAGAGAGACGCCGCCUGGGGUUCACCUUCCCUGGCCUCAGUGUUCUUUACACGUCAAACGGGUCACCCUGAUUUACCUCUCAGUUACUGGAGUCAAAGGAGAUGGACCCGCUGCAGUGCAUAGGAAGGUGCUUAGGUCCGCUCCAAGGAGACACCGCCUCCGCGGUGCCAUCCACGCCAGGGGCCGCGUGACAGCUUGGGGUCCGCGCAGAAGGCUGCCUCAGCGAGGCGGCAGCUGCGCCCCUGCUUUAUCUUUUAGAGGCUGGGAGACUUGGUGCUAUUUCUGGCCUUGGUUUCUAUGUAAAAUCCAGGUUGGUGGGGGAGUUGUGUACACUCCUCUGCCCUAACCUCUUCAUAGGAAGUUAGGUUAAAUCCACAAAGUGGUGGGGACCUUGUUCAAUAGGGAUAGAUUUCACAGGUAGCCCCAAAGUGGGGGAUUUGGCGAAUGUGCCAAUAAACUUGGUUUAAAUUCUAAUUCUGGCUCUGCUACUGGCUUCAGUUACCCUCCCCGAUCUUCCCACCUCAUUCCCUCCCUUCCUCUUUUUUUUUUGAGAUGGGGUCUUGCCCUGUUUCUCAGGCUGGAGUGCGGGGGAAGGUGGGGUCAGUCUUGGCUCACUGCAGCCUGGAACUCCUGGGCUCCAGUGAUCCUCCUGCCUCAGCCUCCCAAGUAGCUGGGACUAAAGACAUGUGCCACCACACCCAGCUAUUUUGUAAAAAGUUUUUGUAGAGAAGGGAUCUUGCUCUGUUGCCCAGGCUGGAGUCUUUUUCUCUUUUUAGAGACACUUUAUCACAUUCACCUCUGCUCUGUAGCAGUGUCUUCAAAGUGAUCUUUCUUUCAAGUGGGGUUGAGUUUGUCUAGAAGGCUCUUGAGCAUUUUCCCAGUGAUAGGGUGAUAGGCCUUACUUUUUUGAAAUUGGGGUAGGGGAAAGAGACAUGAAAAUAUCACAAGUUCUAGAAACCAGGAUUUGAGCAGUCUUGUUGAAGUUGCCCAAUCCCACCUUGAAGUGAUCUGCAUCCAAGAAAAAGGUUUUGUGAUGGUGGUGGUGGAAUGUUUGGGGAUUAAGAGUUUGCUGUGUGGAUUAACAAGCUGGAGCUGGAAAUGUCUAAUGAAACUGACAAUGAUGCCUUCCUGGAUCAACUCACCUGUGUGUCACAUGACAAGCUUGAAGAGGACUCAGGAACAUUCAAACCCAACCUUCUCAUGGAACGGAAGCCCGAAGGGGGCAAAUGCUUAAAGUCACACAGCACAAUGGUUGUGUUGGCCAAAAACCAGAGUUGUCUCCCUCAGUGAUUACAACCAGAUGUAGAAUUAGUUUUGUAUGCCCACCACUCUAUUGCUUUUCCCCCUUAAACUUCUAUUCCUUCUUAUUGGGGGAAGGAGAGCUCCCUUACAGAUGGUGUACGUUAGGGUUUACUGAACCAGGCACCCACACCCUAUUUAGCUUUAGACCUAUACUCUGUUUACAGGAUGGGCAAUCAGCAGCUGAAAACUAAUUGAAUUUGGAAUUAAACCUUUCUCCCUCUACCUAGCUCCCUUCAGCAACUAGUCACUCCCUGGUUCUUGUAUCCACAUGGUGAGUUGUUCAUUAAUAGAACCUUUAGCAGCAAGGCUAGGGGAAGCUGUUUGUACUUGCCAAAGGCCAUUCUCCAUGAACGUAGCUGGGAAUAGGUGACCCCCAAUUUAGAAUGGGGGUGUGUAUAAUUUUCUUAAGAAGUUGGCUGAAGUUUCAUCAUAGUAAUAACUACCAUUUAUUGUGUCUCUAACAUGCCAGCAGCUUUUACAAACAUUAAUUUUUGUGGCUCGAGAAACAACCCUGCAAGGUAGGAGGCAGCAUCCUUGUUCUUAUGGAUGCAGAAUCUGAGAUUCAGCAAGGCUAAGAAACUUGUACAAGGUAAAGUGGCUGGCAAAGAGCAGAGGAUUCAAACCCAGGUCAGUCUGGCCACAAAGUGAUCACACUGCCCUGCUGCCCACUGGAUAUCCAGCUCCAGCCUUGCCUAAGAAAACAUGUUGCUAGUUUUUGAGAAUGAAUGGGAAAGGAGCUGGAACAAAAUAUGCCUGAAUAUCUGACACUUUAUACCAUGGUGUCUGGUGUUUUUGAAUAUUAAGUUUUCUAGAUUGAGGUUAUCACAACUCUUGCCCUUGUCUUCCUUUUUAUUACUUCUAGAGUAAUUGCAGGUUUAACAUCUUCUAUCAUGUUAAAAACAAAGUUAUUUUUCUGAUUAAAAAAUACCUGUUUAUGUAGAAAAUACAGAUGUACAAAGAGGACAAGUCUCAAACUAUAUACCAGCUUCUGGUUAAGAAUGUGUGUACGGGAGCUAGACUUGCAAGGGUAUGUAUCCCUGCUCUGCAAUUUAUGAUUUGUAUGACUUUGGACUAGUCACUUCUGUGCCCGUUUCCUAUCUGUGAAGUUGGAAAUAUCCUACUUUAUUAGGUUAACAUCAAAUGAGUUAAGAGCUGCAAAGCCCCCAAAGUGACUGAGAAGUUUAGUAUUUUAAUAAACUUCUGGUCUUCCUCUCUGAUCUGUGUAUACAUGUGUAAAUAUACAUGUUAGUAUGCAUAUAAGCCAAAGUGAAAUAUUUUUCAAACCAGCUGCUUUUCAUAUAAUUACAUCGUGAUCAUCUUUCCUAACUUCUAAAUAACCUUCUCCAUCACCUGACAAUUGCCUAAAACCCCAUGAUGUGCUGGCGUGAAUGGAACUGAAUCCGUGUUACUGGGCAUGCAGAUUUCCAGUUUUGCACUAACAUAAUGCAUUUUAAAACAAAUUUGAGUAGUUGUUGUGCCAUGAAUGGUAUCUGGGUGACAGGAACUUCAAGCUCUUUUCAGAGCACACCUAAUCCUCCCUCCCCUAGUCUAAAUGAAAAUAAGGAUCAGGAACUACUCCCUUCGGAGCUCAGAACCUGCCUUAAUUCUGAGGCAGCACUGUGAACUUUUCAUACGUCAGCCCUAAGUGGGGAACUCACUCUGGUUCUCCCCUCUCCCUGCCUUCAAAUCUAGAAAAACCAUGUUUCCACGUUUAAUAUCUGAUGUCUCGGUUCCCAAUAAAUCACAAAUCAGAAAGUUCUGUUGUUCCAUUAUUGCUAUGUCUGAGGUGCCCCAUAAGAAGCCUGUCCAUAAAAGGGCUUAGAGGGGAAGCCCUGCUCCCUGUUUCCCAGAUCGGACUCCUAAAUCCUGUCCUUCAGGAUGGAGUGCUGCAAUCCCUUUUAUGCCAUGCUGGGCACUGUACCUCUGCUAUUUUAGUUUUAUGAGAUUCUGAUGACAUGCUUAUUUGACUUUAUUGACACAGAACCCUCCUGCUGGUCUCAAGAUUGGUAGAAACCAUUGAUUAAUCCCCUCUUAACUCCCCCCGCCCCCCGCCCCGCCAACGCCUGCACUGUUUUCCACUACUAGCAAAUCAAUAGGUCAUGUUUAAUGACACUACUCUUGCCUAGCCACUUUCAGGUGUAUUAUAUAUGCAGACUCAAGGGAUGUAUUUGUCCAUUGCGUCUGAGCUCCAAAGAGGCAAGAGUGAUGGGCAGAAGUGAUUUGGGGUCAGUAGUCAUGGAGUAUACCUCUUAAAAGGUUUACAGCUUUAAUGAGAUUUUUCUCCUACUGUCUUAGACAAGAAAUCUCCAAAUGUUGGAAACUUGGUGCUUUAAACAGUAUACGUUCUAAAGGAAUUCAACCGCAUUUCAGGACCUGUUGACUGACCAACCUCAGACACAGCCAUAUCCGAAGACAUUAAAGGAGAGGGCUUGAUGUUCCAAUUGAGGGAGCGCAUCAUCGUCUCUCAGAAAGAGUCUAAUAUGGGAUUCCUGGUCACCUCCCUUGCUCUUUUCUUCCUGGAUGAAACAAGAAGAUAAUCAGGGUGUCUGUGCACACCAGGACUCAGAAGACAAAGGGAUGGGUUCUGAUUUUGAGGACUCUGAGGACAGGGAAGGGGACCCAGAAGAAAGAGAAAUGGGCUCUAAUCCACAUGACACAAACAAGAGAGAAGGCCAUCCGGAGCCGGAGAUGGGCUCCAACCCACAGGACUCAAGGCACAGGGAAGCAGUGCCCGACAUCUGCACAGAGGGGCAGCUGAGUGAGGAAGAAGGCGUUUCUGUCCGUGGGGAAGAGGAUGACCAAUCCGGUGUAGCUGACAUGGCGAUGUUCCCAGGACUGUCUGAGUCUGACAGCAUAUCCCGGAGCCUCCGGGAGGACGACGACGAGAGUGCUGGGGAGAACCGGCUGGAGGAGGAAGAGGAGCAGCCGGCCCCUCCCGUACUUCCCUGGAGGCGACAUCUCUCCCUGGGGAGUCGGCACCGAGGUGACAAGCCCGCCCACCGCCGCUUCCACCGGCUCCACCACCCCAUGGCCGUGGACCUCGGGGAGCUGGAUAGCCUGGUGGCCAGCAUCAUGGACGCGCCCACCAUCUGCCCCGACUGCGGGGAGAGCUUCAGUCCUGGCGCCGCCUUCCUGCAGCACCAGCGCAUUCACCGCCUGGCUGAGGCCGCUGCCGCCGCCAGCCUGGAGCCCUUCGGCCUGGCGGGCGAGUGCGACGCGAUGGUGGGCAUGAUGGGGGUGGGUGUGGCGGGGGGCUUCGGGGCCGGGCCCCCGCUGGCCCGGCCCCCGCGCGAAAAGCCCUUCCGCUGCGGGGAGUGCGGCAAGGGCUUCAGCCGCAACACCUACCUGACCAACCACCUGCGCCUGCACACGGGCGAGCGGCCCAACCUGUGCGCCGACUGCGGCAAGAGCUUCAGCUGGCGCGCCGACCUGCUCAAGCACCGGCGCCUGCACACGGGCGAGAAGCCCUACCCGUGCCCCGAGUGCGGCGAGGCCUUCAGCCUCAGCUCGCAUCUGUUGAGCCACCGGCGCGCGCACGCGGCGGCCAGCGGCGCGGGGGCGGCGGCGCUGCGGCCCUUCGCCUGCGGGGAGUGCGGCAAGGGCUUCGUGCGCCGUUCGCACCUGGCCAACCACCAGCGCAUCCACACGGGCGAGAAGCCGCACGGCUGUGGCGAGUGCGGCAAGCGCUUCAGCUGGCGCUCGGACUUGGUGAAGCACCAGCGCGUGCACACGGGCGAGAAGCCCUACAUGUGCUCCGAGUGCGGCGAGACCUUCAGCGUCAGCUCGCACCUCUUCACGCACAAGCGCACGCACUCGGGUGAGCGGCCCUACGUGUGCCGCGAGUGCGGGAAGGGCUUCGGGCGUAACUCGCACCUGGUGAACCACCUGCGCGUGCACACCGGCGAGAAGCCCUUCCGCUGUGGCCAGUGCGAGAAGCGCUUCAGCGACUUCUCCACGCUCACGCAGCACCAGCGCACGCACACGGGCGAGAAGCCCUACACGUGCAUCGAGUGCGGCAAGAGCUUUAUCCAGAGCUCCCACCUGAUCCGCCACCGCCGCAUCCACACGGGCAACAAGCCGCACAAGUGUGCGGGCUGCGGCAAAGGCUUCCGCUAUAAAACGCACCUCGCGCAGCACCAGAAGCUGCACCUGUGUUAGGGGCUGGGUCCGCGGGAGGCUGCCGUCUGGGGAGCCUGUGGGGGGUAGAUAUCCUGGGACUGACCCAGGGGAAGGAAGUGGGGAAGGGGCGGGAGGGACAAUCUGAGAGUGACUGGGGAGCCUUUGGUGUUUGGGGUUUCCUGAAGUGGGAGGAGUGUUGAGUAAGUUGGUCUUUCCCGGUGCUAUACUUGCCUCCUCUCCACGGAAGAAUUGUUCAGGAGAUGCGCUUGGGGUGAUGACUUCCUUAAAUACACGCUGUAGGGGGUGAAGAGCUUGGAGGACCAGGCACUUUGAGGAAGGGCAGUUCGUGGGCUGGGGUGGGAACAGGAUGGCGGGCAAUAGACUAGGGUAGGCCGCGAUGGCCUGUAGAAGGUUGCGGGGAGAGGGUUUAAAUGAGGGUUAUGGGGCGAAAUAAAACCAAGUAUAAGUGAUUCUAUCUUGGUCCCACCAAGAGUUUGCCCGAUCUCCACACAUCACCUGUUGUCUCACAAAAAGUAGGGGAACCUUGUCAGUCACAUAGGACAGGAUAUUUAAUGUACUUUUCCUUUCUCUGAGCCACAGUUAGCUGCUAUUUUGAGGCAUCCAAGGGGAAGUGGGCUGAAAAACGCCACACUCAUUUCAAGGGGCAAUGUCUGGGGUUUAGAAAUUCAUUUAUAACUGGUUCUCUGAUGUGGGAAAUCCUGAUUCUGUCCCGGGUUCUUUGCUACUUCCUUGAAAAUACUCUAGCUUCAUGCUGGGUCAAGGUGGUUUACCUGGAUGACCCCCCUCCCCCGCCCUCGCCCAUCCCAGGUGUGUGCCACACCCAGUAUUUCUUUCAGGUCUCAACUGUGGUGUUUUAAGUGCAGGGAAAAGGAACAAUCACAGCUAUGUGUGACUUUCCUUUUCCCACCUCACCUUGAUGUAGGUGUUUCAAGUGAACUUUAGACCAACAGUUGCCCAGUGACCUGCUAAAAAGUCAACUAGCUCAGAGUUUUGCUGGCCUUUAUGUGAGAAAUCCAAGAAAGUGUUCACUUUUUUGGGAUGCGAGACUCCUUGGUCUCAUUUGCCUUCACUUUGCAUUUGUUAGUGACCUCCACUAACCCCCACUUCCAUGCAUAUUGACGAGGGAUCUAGUCUAAGUAAGAAUGUCUUUUGCCUGCGCGUGGAGGCACAGUAGAAAUCUCAAGGCUUUACCCAGAAGAGCCCAGUCAGGGAGAGGUGUAAAUGCAAAAUUGCCAAAUAGCACAAACAAUGAAUGUUUUCUGGUUGUUAUAUAGAUGCCAAAAUAGCACUUUGAUAUUUGCAAAGUGCUUUAUGCUUUUUAAUAAUUGUUAGCUGUUUCUCACAUCAUUGUGAGUUAGAUCAGUAUUAUGACCGCUGUCUUAGGGAAGGCCUGGGAACAGGAGUGUGCAGGCUGUCCUGAAGAGAGGCUGAGGACAGUGUGAAUAAUUGUAGCCUGACCUUUUGCAUUCUCCAGCUCAGCUGCUAGGAAGACUUACUUGUCAUGAUUUAUAUAAUAAAAUUAAGGACACUGAAAAUUCUUAUGCUUGAUGAAAAACUUAAGGCUAGCCUAGAAGGGCCAAACAUGUCCUUAUUGACAAAGCUGGUCUUUGUCGCCUAAUUAGGGUAUCCUAGCUAUGUUCCAUUUCUAGUAAGGGGCUGUAGUUAGAUGACUCUUGUAUAGAUUUCAGUUACUUAUGCUGAAGAUCCCUGUGCUAGGUUAGCCUUUAGAAGUUAGAGUUGUGGAAAGCAGUAUUGUUUUCUUCUCUAGUGAUUGUUACCCUACACAUUUCAUGGAAGCAUCUUCACAAAAUAUCAGACACAGUGGAAGGGGGAAAAAAAGCUACGAGAUUGUUUUUACACUUUUAGCAAAGUUUCUGUGGAUGCUAGUAAUUUAUACUUGAUCAGUUGUAUUCUAGUAAAGAACCUCUUUGGGGACUGUAGGAAAGCAUGUUUUUGUGGUUAUAAAAACACUUAAAAAUCCUGAUAAUUCUGGGCUUGUAUAAUGCCUGUUGAUCUUGCCCUCUUAAUCAGUUUAUUGUUAUUCACAAAUGCAAAUAGGUUUUCAAACUACAGACAGUUUUGAAAGACAUUAAUUCUCAUUUUCUUCUAGUCAGGAGUAAUACAAGCAAACAAGUGUCCGUUUUGAAUUCUGAUUUGUAAUCUGAAUACUAAACAUAUUAGACCCACCUGAAAAUAAUAUAGCCAAUUUCUAGGUAAUCUUACUGCUUUGUGGGUUUCUUUCCAUGUACAUCUACCUCUUCCAGCUGUUUUAAGUUUUCUCAAGUCUGUGCCUAUGAAAUCUCAUCCAACUUUUGAUUAUUCAUGGAUUGAUUAUCCGCUUUUUUUUUGCUUUUUUGCUGCCAUUGCUAUGCCUGGUCUCGUCUGCAUCAAAUAUACUACAUAUCAGCAACUUUAGAGAAUGGGUUCAACAGGGAGUGGAGAGUGAAGCUAAUGUAAAAUAGUUUAGUGGCAGUGGGAAUCUUUGGACUUCAUUUACCUCUCUCAUUAUUUCUAUUACCAUGGAUAAAAAAGUCAGCUGCUACGUUGAUAUCCCUUCUAUGAGCACAUUCUUAGCAGAAGAAAACAAUCCAACUACCAACACCCGACUCUAUUGGUGCAUUUAAAAUGUGAUUCCAUUUUUUCUUACAAUUCUUCAGGGAACUUACCUGCAUUAAGUGAGGUUAAAUGCAUUCAGGAGGUUGUUUGUUUCUUCUAUCUAGUUUUAGAAUAAUAUUUCUUCGGCAAACCCUGCUAACUGCGGUUCACCCUUGAAAACGUUAAUCUGAGGACUUUUUCCACCAACUCAUUAAUGAUGGUGGAAGCAAGUGUAUUAUUUGUUUCCUGGAGAAUUUGAUGAAGAGCAGUCUUCCUCUGCUGCCCUUUACUAAGCAAAACCUGGAGCAAUUUAAAUAGGCUAAAUGGUUUUGAUUAAAUCUUGAGCUCCGAGUUGGAAGGAGAAAAUGAGAAGUUAACCCCUUGAGCCAUGUGGUCUCUUUACAAUCAAGAGACUGUACAUAUGUGAAAAAAUACAAAUUAAGGACCUGUGUUCAUAGACAAUCUAAACUGUGUUUCUGAAGUUUGUGCACAUUUUUCUUCACUGUAAUGUUAUUUUACAGCUGUUUGUUAAAAUAGUGAAUAAUUUAAUGAUCCUAAAAGUAACAGGUUUCGUGUGAGUGUGCUUGUAUACGUGAGAUUUGCCUUAUUUUCAGGUUGUUUUAUUUAACGAUGGUUCCUUGGACAGCAUUCUGGUGUUCAGCAACCAAUAUGGAAUAUUUGUCAUUAAAUCCAUAUCAGUCUUUUACCAUGUCAUUCUUCUUUGCCACACAUUAAAUGUCACUCAGCUCUA